CCCCGGCAACCCGCGGCCGCCGCCAUGGACGCGCUGUUGGGCACAGGGCCUCGCCGGGCUCGCGGCUGCCUGGGCGCGGCUGGACCCACGUCUUCAGGUCGCGCGGCGCGGACCCCGGCGGCGCCCUGGGCGCGCUUCUCCGCCUGGCUGGAGUGUGUGUGCGUGGUCACCUUCGACCUGGAGCUGGGCCAGGCGCUGGAGCUGGUGUAUCCGAACGACUUCCGGCUCACAGACAAGGAGAAAAGCAGCAUCUGCUACCUGUCUUUUCCCGACUCGCACUCAGGCUGCCUUGGAGACACUCAGUUCAGCUUCCGCAUGCGCCAGUGUGGAGGGCAGAGGAGCCCCUGGCAUGCCGACGACAGGCACUACAACAGCAGGGCCCCUGUGGCACUGCAGAGGGAGCCGGCACACUACUUCGGCUACGUGUACUUCAGGCAGGUGAAGGACAGCUCUGUGAAGAGGGGCUACUUCCAGAAGGCCCUAGGGUCCAGCCCCACCGGCCGCCACCCAGGGAGUUCAGUGUUGGGUUUUCUCCUGUCUAAUAAUUCUGGGGUCCAAGUCAGGCGUUCCUGGGGCAGCUGUCCUGUGAAGUUGGUGGGACGUGCUACCCUGGGCCAGCUCCAGUCUUUGGUGCUGGUGUCCCGCUUGCCCUUUGUCCGGCUGUUCCAAGCGCUGCUAAGCCUCAUCGCCCCCGAGUACUUUGACAAGCUGGCGCCCUGCCUGGAAGCAGUGUGCAGUGAGAUCGACCAGUGGCCGGCGCCUGCACCUGGGCAGACCCUGAACCUACCUGUCAUGGGCGUUGUUGUCCAGGUGCGCAUCCCAUCCAGGGUGGACAAGUCCGAGUCCAGUCCUCCGAAGCAGUUUGACCAAGAGAACCUGCUGCCAGCCCCAGUGGUUCUUGCUAGCGUCCACGAGCUGGACCUGUUCAGGUGCUUCCGGCCUGUGCUGACUCAUAUGCAGACACUGUGGGAGCUCAUGCUCCUCGGGGAGCCCCUGCUAGUCCUGGCACCCUCGCCCGACGUGUCCUCGGAGAUGGUGCUGGCCUUGACCAGCUGCCUGCAGCCCCUCAGGUUCUGCUGCGACUUCCGUCCCUACUUCACCAUCCAUGACAGCGAGUUCAAGGAGUUCACCACACGCACGCAGGCCCCACCAAACGUGGUCCUGGGAGUCACAAACCCUUUCUUUAUCAAAACACUCCAGCACUGGCCCCACAUCCUCCGAGUCGGGGAGCCCAAGAUGUCAGGAGACCUGCCUAAGCAAGUCAAGCUGAAAAAGCCUUCAAGGUUGAAGACCCUGGACACCAAGCCAGGCCUCUACACCGCUUACACGGCCCACCUCCACCGCGACAAGGCGCUGCUCAAACGGCUGCUCAAGGGCGUGCAGAAGAAGCGGCCGUCAGAUGUGCAGAGCGCCCUGCUGCGGCGGCACCUCCUGGAGCUCACCCAGAGCUUCAUCAUCCCCCUGGAGCACUACAUGGCCAGCCUCAUGCCCCUGCAGAAGAGCAUCACGCCCUGGAAGACUCCCCCCCAGAUCCAGCCCUUCAGCCAGGAUGACUUCCUGCGUAGCCUGGAGCAUGCUGGGCCCCAGCUCACCUGCAUCCUCAAGGGCGACUGGCUGGGUCUCUACAGGUGCGUGGACUGCAGGCGGUUUUUCAAGUCCCCCCAUUUUGAUGGCUGGUACCGGCAGCGGCACAAGGAGAUGGCCCUGAAGCUGGAGGCCCUGCACCUGGAGGCUAUCUGUGAGGCGAACAUCGAGACCUGGAUGAAAGACAAGUCCGAGGUGGAGGUCGUGGACCUGGUCCUGAAACUUCGUGAGAAGCUGGUGCGGGCUCAGGGCCACCAGCUCCCUGUGAAGGAGGCUACGCUGCAGCGGGCACAGCUGUACAUCGAGACGGUCAUCGGCUCCCUGCCCAAAGACCUGCAGGCUGUCUUGUGCCCUCCCUAGAACAAAGCCAAGGGCCACGGUCCCAGGGCCCUAGGUCUGCCUGAGCCUCCCACUCCCCAGUGGUGGCGGCACUGGGCCAAGCACACGCUCCCCUUCCUUGGCCCCCCGCCCAGACUGCAGGCUCCCCUUCCUGCACCACCAUUGUCUCAGCAGUAAAGGCGACAUUUGGAACCACAGCAUGGCCUUGACCAUAGGGGUUCCUCGCAGGCAGAGCCUUGCCUCCUCCUGGGUCCCACCUGGCCUCUGCAGACCUUAGGCUGGGACGGGGGCGGGGACAGGCUGGGAGCCCUUGCUGAUGUGGGUGCGUCUACCGUCUGCCCCUCCCGGUGCCCAUCUGUUGGCCCCCGACCCCCCUGCGCUGUGUGUGAUGCUUCCCUCAGCCCAACAGGCUGCCCAGGACAGGAGGGACCCUCUCCUGACACAGCCCCCGUCUUGUCUGGGGAUGGGAGGCUAUUUUGCAUAUAGUCAUCAACUUGAGAAAGGGAGAGACCACUUUGCAGUGUGAAGAGCUCUGCUCACCACCCCUGGUGCUCCUCUGGACACCCACCUGCUUGGGGCUGUGGUUUGUUGGGAGGUAGGGGUUGGGCAGGGGGCUGUGUGCAGCCCAGCACCUCUGCUAGGAGAGCUGGCUCAGCCUGGCUCUCGGAGAGCCACAGCACCUUCCUGGCUCCCAGUCCUGGAGCCCCCACCAGGCACCAGCUCCGUGCGUCCCUUCUGGGAGGUGGACAGGGCUCCUGUUGUCCAAGUGUGUCCGUCCAUCCCCCACAUGCAGCCCAAGGGGCUCUGGACUUCGGCCUGACCCUGCCUCUGGCUGGAGCCUGCAUGUCUCCCUUUCCUUGGUAAGGGGUGAACGUCCCUAAGAGCCACCUCUGGGUUGUAUGCUCCCCCCGUGACACCUGCAGGCACUGAGGCCGGUGAGGUACGGUGUUGACCCUGCACAGCACACAGUGACGGUACUGUCAGGGCUCCGGACAGCCAAGCCCUGCUCAGCAUCACGCACUGUGUGCCCGGGAGCAGGUCCCCUGACCACUCAGACCCUCAGACUCCUCAUCUGAGCGAGCCAGCCAUGCAGAUGCCCGACAGGGUGCUGGGAGGGCCACUCAUGGAGACUGGGCUUUGUACCCUGUGAGGCCGGGCGGGUGCUGGCCAGGGGACACAGGGCUGGGGGAGGGACUUUUUCUUUUUUUUUCUUUUUGAAAUGGAGUCUCGCUCUGUUGCCCAGGCUGGAGUGCAGUGGCAUGAUCUCGGCUCACUGCAAGCUCUGCCUCCCGGGUUCACGCCAUUCUCCUGCCUCAGCCUCCCGAGUAGCUGGGACUACAGGCACCCACCACUGCGCUUGGUUAAUUUUUUGUAUUUGUAGUAGAGACAGGGUUUCACCAUGUUAGCCAGGAUGGUCUCGAUCUCCUGACCUCGUAAUCCGCCCGCCUCGGCCUCCCAACGUGCUAGGAUUACAGGCAUGAGCCACCGCGCCCGGCCGGGACUUUUCUUUUUCUUCUGAGGCCCCCAUUCAGUCCGAGGAAUGUAGCCUUCAUUCAGCGCAACGUACUGUUUGUGUUCUCAUUGGUGCUCUCAGACCUCCAGCCAGGUGGUGGAGAGCGAGCACUGCCAGCCACUUCAGUGCAGGAUGUGACUGAGCCACAAGGACAGCGGGGUCAGGUGUCCGGGCGCCAGGUAGUUCUCAGAACUUGGUACAUGUCAACUUGUCCAGCCCAACUGCAGCCCAGGACAGCCUGUCCCUGUUCCCAUUCUACAGACAAGACGCGGAGGCAGCCGGGAGGGUGACCAAGGGGAGCUGUUAAGCCCCAGAUGUCUGGUGCAGGGUCCAAGGAUGUGACCACAUGAAACAGAACACAUAGAGGCCGAGGUGGCAAACCUGUUCUGUGGCAGGGACAAGCCGGGGACCCGAGGGUGAGAAAGGUCCUGGCCCCAAAUGCAGCUUGGGCCUCCUGACUGUAGCACAGGGGGACCAGCCUCCCCACUGAGGGCUUGGUCUCUAGAGGGUCUGCAGAGAUGCUGGCACCUCUUGUGUGGGCAGCUUGAAUGCUGACCUCCAUAAGAUGGGGCCUGGGGGGCCAGUACAGGCCCUGCCAUCAGCUGCCCUCCACCAGGGCCCUCUGCAAAAGCCUUAUGCUGGUGACCAGCCCCCUGAGGACCACCACUUCAAGGUGUCGGGGCAGCUUGGGAAGACAACCCACCUCUCUCACAACUGUGACCCCACUUUGGGGAGCGCACCCCAAGGACCGUGGCAGCAUGUGCUUCCCCACAGCACAGUCUCGCCUCACUUGGCUUUCUGAGGGCUGCCGCACAGCACAGAGGGCUGCAGACCCACAUGGCUGCAGGGGAGGGGCUUCAGGCUGGUCUCUGAGGAGCCCCCAGGGACCCUGGCCACUGUGUAUCCAGAAAUGCACAAGCAGAUUUCCCUGGAGGGCUCUGGUGAGGCCACAUAGUGGCGUGUGAAGGGGGAACUUGAGGGGGGAACCGGGCUGGGUGGCCAGCAUUGCCCUGGGCAGAAGCUAAGGCUAAGGUGGGGGGUAGUGUCCCAGCCCCUCUUCCUCAGGGCCUGUCCCCACCUGUGCAGAAGAGGCCUGGGGUGGAAUGUGGCCUGGGGUGGAUGGGUGGGGGCUGGGCGUGGAGACCUGCCAGCUCCAUCUGUCCGGAUGCCUCUUGUGGCCCCCCCAGUGUCAGGGCCGCUCUGAGUUGGCUGAGCCUCUGUCCAGGGCUAGGCCAUGGCCCUCCCCGCCCCACGCACUCCAGGCCAGGGGCAGUCAGUGAAGAGGCAGGAAGGUCCAGACAGCUCUACCCCUGGCCAGAGUGCCAGCCCCCGCAGGCAAGAGGGCUUGCUGGGCAGAACUUAGUUGGCGAGGGUGAGGACUGCUGUGGUCACAGGCCUCCCGAAGGACAGGGACCACAGAACCUAGAGGGUGGGAAGGGCUGGGAGCAGGUCUGGAGUGGGGCUCGGGGCUGAGGGUGCACACAGGGGGCCUGCUCAGGGACAGGAAGGACAGCUGCUCACCCUCAAGCUUCCUGCUGGCUAUUUAAAGACUCCCUUUUAGUCUAGAACAGUGGCCUUCCCACAGUUUUGGUAUUAAAAUGUCCUUUUGUGACUGGA